CUAUGCCCACUGCUGUCAACCCAGUCAGGGCCCUUAUCACUUUAUUCUUGAAUUACUUCAGUUCUCCAUUUUUUUUCUCAUGUGGUGUUUUUCAAACUUGAGUGUUGAUUGGAAUCCCAGGGUUAAUUCAACUUUAAUUUUAUGAAUAUGAUUUCAUAUAAGUUCCUUAUGAUAAAACCAGAGCAGAUUUACAAAUUAAAUAUAGACCAUCAAAUUAGCUGUACAUAUUUAAGGAUGAGAUUUUGUUAAAACCAAAUAGUCAAUGUUAGAGCUUAUAGAAUGGCAUAGCCUCAGGAUCAGCUUUAUAAUCAGUUUUUUUAAAUUUGGCUUGAUAAUACUAACAGAGAAUGGCUAUUUGCAUAAAUAUGUUUUAUAAAAUGGUGUUAACUUUUAGUCUUUGUUCAGGAUAAUGAGACCUACUAGUUAACCAGAACGGGGCCAGCAAGCAACUCUUGAAUGCUAGUUUUAAUGCCUGAUCAAAAUUCUGUAAAGCUGUGUUGAUCACUGAGGCGUUGCGGAUAUACUGAGCCUGCAUUAAGUGGAUAUUUAAUCUAAUUAUUUCUGGAAUCUUUACCAGAAAACAUGCUCUUACAUAGUUUGCUCCUGGGUUUGCUGUUGGUGAACUGCCGUUGGUUGGUGGGAUCUCUGUGUCCCAUGGGCUUUGCCACACAGCUGGGGCUCUGAGUACUUCAGCUCACAUUCCUUUGUUUGCCACCCUUGCCUUAACUCACUUACCUGUAUUGUUUUUUCUCCCAUAGCACUCAACAUCAUCUUACAUGUAAACAUUUUACUUUGUUGUUGUUGUUGUUGUUGUUGUUGUUGUUUUUGAGACAGAGUCUUGCUCUGUUGCCCAGGCUGGUGCAGUGGCACAUCUUGGCUCACUGAAAUCCCUGCUUCCUGGGCUCAAGUGAUUCUCAUGCCUCAGCCUCCUUAGUAGCCGGGACUACAGGUGUGUGCCACCACUCCUGGCUAAUUUUUGUAUUUUUAGUAGAGACGGGGUUUCACCGUCUUGGCCAGGCUGGUCUUGAACUCCUGGCCUCAGGUCAUCCACCUGCUUCAGCCUCCCAAAGUGCUGGGAUCACAGGCAUGAGCUACUGCACCUGACACUUUGUUUUUAACUGUUUCUGUCCAACUAGAUUUUAAGCUGUAUAAGGGCACAGAUUUUUAAUUGUUAAUUGCUAAGUCUUCAGUUUCUAUUGUAGUCUCUGGCUUGUAUUAGAUGCUCAAUAAAUAUUUGUUGACUUAAUGAAUGCAUAUUAACCCUUCUUUUCUUUAUUCAACUGCAAACUCAAAUACUCUUUUCUGAGUUGUGUGCUCUCACUGUGGGUAAAGACCAGUUUUUCUCUUCAUUUUAAACACAACUAAACUGGCCCUGAAUUGUAUAGAAUCCUUUUGAUUUGUUGUUUGAUCAGUACAAGUUCAGUCAGUGGCACAGUUACUUCCCUUGAUUCAGAUUCUGUAGAAGCCUAAAAGUGCAUUAUCUCUUCAAGUAGACAUGUCAUCAUAUAGGCUGCUAUGGAGAUCUUUUUUUUUCCUUUUAAAUUGUUUGUGUAACAGUUUCUGUUUUAAAACAGUGGAAUUACCAGCCUGGACACUAUAGUGAGACACUUUCUCUACAAAAAAUAAAUUAAAAAAAAUUAGCUGGGUGUGGUGGAGUACACCUGUAGUCCCCAGCUACUCGAGAGGCUGAGGCAGAAAGAUUGCCUGAGCCCAGGAAUUUGAGGCUUCAGUGAGUUGGGAUUGCAUCACUGCACUCCAGCCUGGACGACAGAGUGAGACCUUGUCCCUUCCAAAAAAAUUGAAAAAGUAGAAUUAUAUUUGGGAGUUUUUUUCCUCAAAUUCCUUUGAAGUUAAGAUUUAUAAAAGUAUGGGAGGCCAAGCUGGGAUUAUCAUUUGGGCCCAGAUGUUCCAGGCUGCAGUGAGCUACGGUCGGGCCACGGAACUCCAGCCUGGGGAACAGAGUGAGCCCUGCCUCAAAAUAAUAAUAAAAAUAAUAAUAAUAGUACAAGCUCUCUUAAUUACUACCUGUUUUUUUUUUGAGACAGAGUCUUGCUCUGUCACCCAGGCUGGAGUGCAGUGGCGCUAUCUAGGCUCAUUGCAAGCUCUGCCUCCCGGGUUCACGCCAUUCUCCUGCCUCAGCCUCCCGAGUAGCUGGGACUACAGGUGCCCGCCACCACGCCUGGCUAAUUUUUUGUAUUUUUAGUAGAGAUGGGGUUUCACCUUGUUAGCAAGAAUGGUCUCGAUCUCCUGACCUCGUGAUCUGCCUGCCUUGGCCUCCCAAAGUGCUGGGAUUAUAGGCGUGAGCCACUGCGCCUGGCCACUACCUGUUUUUUUUUUUAAUCCUAUGUUUUUAAAUAAUUCUAAUCAUCUAUUCAUAUUUUUUGUUUCUCCUAUUUAACAUUUUAUGUAACAUUUUUAGAUUUUAAAAUUUGUUUCUGUUAUCACUUCUAAAAGUGAAUGUUAUUUUUAAAAAUGAAUGCCUUUACAUUGGGUUGUUAUGUAACCUAAUUUGCUUUAACAAAUAACUUUAUUUUGGAGUAAUUUUAUUUUUAAUUAUUUAUUUAUUUAUUUAUUUAUUUGGGACGGAGUCUCGCUCUGUCGCCCAGGCUGGAAUGCAGAGGUGCGAUCUCUGCUCACUGCAGCCUCCACCUCCUGGGUUCAAGCAAUUCUCCUGCCUUAGCCUCCCAAGUAGCUGGGAUUACAGGUGCUCGCCAUCAUGCCCAGCUAAUUUUUGUAUUUUUAGUAGAGACUGGGUUUCACCAUAUUGGCCAGGCUGCUCUUGAACUCCUGACUUACGUGAUCCGCCUGCCUCAGCCUCCCAAAGUGCUGGGAUUAACAAGCAUGAGCCACUGCACCUGGCCUAUUUUGGAAUACUUUUGGAUUUAUAUAGCCAUGGUAUAUUUGUUAAAACUAAGAAAUCAGUAUCAGUAUGUUGUCAUUAACUAAACUCAAGACUUUAUUUGGAUUUUGCCAGUUAUUCCACUAAUGUCUUUCUUUGGUUGGUUGGUUGGUUGGUUUCAGGAUCCAAUCCAAGAUACCACAGUUCAUUUAGUUAUCAUGUCUCCUAAGUUUUUCUGAUCUGUGGUUGUUCUCAGCAUUUCCUUAUUUUUCAUGACCUCUUAAUCGUUUUAAAGUGUAUUGGUCAGAUGUUUUGUAAGAAUGUCCUUUGAUUUCGGCUUAUCGGAUGUUUUCUUAUGAUUAGGCUGAAGUUAUGGGUUGAGGUCUGGGGGAAGGAUACCACAGAGGUGAAAUCCCCAUCUCAUUUCAUCACAUCGGGGAGUACAUAAUGACAGCAGUACUUACCAUUGCUCAUGUUAAUGGUUAUGGUUUUUUUUCACAGAAACAUUACUGUUUCCCUUUCCAGACUCUUCUUUGGAAGUGAAUCAUUGAAUCUAGCUCACGCUCAGGGGGAAGGAAAUUGAAUUCUCCCUCCCAGAAUGGGGACAUACACUCAUGUAUCAGUUGGAAUUCUUGUCAGGAGAGUUGUUCCUUCUCCUCCAGUUGUUUAUUUAAUCACUUAUUUAUAUCAUAGACUCAUGAAUAAUUAUUUUAUUCUGUUAUAAUACUGUUAUGAUUUACUCUGCUGCUCAAAUUAUUCCAGCUUUGGCCACUGAGAGUUUCUUCUGUUUGCUUCCAGUCUCGGACCUAUCCGUCUCCUUUCAUCUUUGGAGCAUUUCCCUUCUUCUACUGGCUUGCCUUGUAGUUUCCCUGUCCCAACCCUAGAAUCAGCUGUUUCUGCAGACCCUGCUUCCUUGUAUUUAUUGGAAGGUGGUAUUUAGAAACAAAAGUCUUGGGUGCAGGGUAUGCUUAUUUUAUUGCUCCUGGGGUGUCACUGCUUCCAGGCCCUCUGUUGGACAGACCCUGGAAAUGCAGGUAUUUCAGCUAACCUGCAUGUGCAUACAUACCUACGUUUCUGUAUCUAUCCGCAUAUAUUUUAAAAUACACGUGAGUUCAUAUUGAUAUAUCUGACUAAUUCAUCACCACCUCUUGCUUAUUUGUAACUUCUUUCUGUGACAUUGAGAAACUUGGCACACAUUAUCUACAUUUUAUUUACUUAUUUGUUUAACCCUAGUGUACAUGUAGAGUAUUUUCAGAAUUACAGACUGGUACCCUUAUGAGAAACAAAUUUACCAGCUAGAGUACAGAGUAGAUUGUCCAAAGUUCUGUAGAUUAGCUCCCCCCGACCUCCUGCUCCUUCCAUGAGAUUAUCUCAUAAAAUUAUAAUACUGUUAGACUUGCUGUAUAGUUUGCAUUCUAUCCUGAGAUCCCCUGACAUCCUGUUUUGUUUUUAUUUGCAUACAGUUUACCAUUUAAAAAAAGUCUUUAUAUUGAGUUGUUAACUUUUUAAUAUAAAUGUUGUAAUUCCUGAUAUUACUCAUCUGCCAUUUAUGUAGUUGAUAGUCACUACUUUUUUUUUUUUUUUUUUUUUUUUGAGAUGGAGUCUUGCUCUGUCGCCUAGGCUGGAGUGCAGUGACGUGUUCUCAGCUCACUGCAACCUCCGCCUCCUAGGUUCAAGCGAUUCUCCUGCCUCAGCCUCCUGAGUAGCUGGGAUUACAGGCGUGCAUCACCACGCCCGGAUAAUUUUUGUAUUUUUAGUAGAGACGGGGUUUCACCAUGUUGGGCAGGCUGGUCUUGAACUCUUGACCUCAUGAUCCACCUGCCUCGGUCUCCCAAAGUGCUGGGAUUACAGGCGGGAGCCACAGCGCCCACCUGAUAGCCACUACUUUUUUAAUGCUGAUAUAGUGCUUACCAUCUGUCAGGCACUGUCUAUGCACCGUAAAUAAAUUUACUUCUCACAAUGACUCUGAGGUGGAGGCUCUUGAAUUAGCCUUUUUUCAUGAGGAGAGUGAGGCACAAAGAUGUGCAGUAACUUGGCCAACUUCACACCCAGCUGCUAAGUGGGAGAACUUGGAUCUGAACCCAGGGAAUGAGCUUUGGAGUCCAAACUCUUGCUUUUUGUUUAAUGCUGUGUAUAGGACUUAGAAUUAAUACAACUAACUCUUCUCUUAUUAGUUUAGUUUAUUACUUGGAAUUUGGUGUGAAAUAGAGAGUGCUGCUACCCCAAUUCUUUGCCCCAUGUGUGUAACAGGCAUUAUUAAUCAUGACAGCACUCUCUCUGCUGAGCUAGAACAUGGCCUGGCCUAAGGCCAAUAAUCCUUAUGGACACAACCCUCAAAGUGGUUGUAUGAGAUGAACUCUCCUUGCCAUCUCUGAUCUUGUCUGUUUUGAAUCCUGAUUCUAGUGCCCAGUGCAUGGCACUGCGUGCCUGCUUCUCCUGGAUUCCUCUCUCAUGGUCUUCCUUUUUACAGGGACAGGUUUUCUAUAUUCCCCCUCAGGCAUAGGAUCUGUUUCUCUUAAGUAAUUAAUUUUUAUCACUUACCAAUAAUUUAACAUCUAUAUGUCUAAGUUCUCUUUAUAUUGUUUUUCUUAUCCUUACCUACAAAAUCUCAUUUACCAUUGAUUUAAAUUUCAGUAUAUUGAAACAAUGGAUUGUAACAUUAAAAAUAAAUGAAAUUGCCAAAUGAUACUAACAGCUGCCUUCAAAGCAUUUAAACAUACAAACAGGCACUAUUGAAGACUGGAGAGUUAUCAAAAUUGGCAAUUUUUUGGCAGUCUUGCUGUGAAGUAAACAUUUUUAAAAGGAAGGACAUUGAGAAUAUUGUAAUCAUAUUACUUACAUCUUGUUGGGUUUGGAUUUGACCUUACAUAGCCUGGUAUUCAGUUAAGAGUCAAAGUUGCUGCUAUUAAUUUAGUUGAGAAGGAUAAAUAGUACAUGUAGUUUAUUGUUUUCUUUAGAGAAAUAGAAACAGAAACAUUUAUUUGGCCAGACCAAAUAGGUGGUCAUUCCCUUGAUUUAGCAAAUCCUUGAGGUAGAAUUUUUUUUUUUUUUUUUUGAGACGGAGUCUCACUGUGUCGCCCAGGCUGGAAUGCAGUGGCACGAUCUCGGCUCACUGCAAGCUCUGCCUCCCGGGUUCACGCCAUUCUCCUGCCUCAGCAUCCCGAGUAGCUGGGACUACAGGUGCCCGCCACCACGCCUGGCUAAUUUUUUGUAUUUUUAGUAGAGACGGGGUUUCACUGUGUUAGUCUCGAUCUCCUGACCUCAUGAUCUGCCCAUCUUGGCCUCCCAAAGUGCUGGGAUUAUUGGCGUGAGCCACCGCGCCUCCCGGUAGAAUUUUUAAAGAAGCAAUAAGGGCUCUGACAAUACCUAUGGGACUUUUUUCAAAUUAUUCAGUUAUUGGCAGCUGGGUAAAGAGGGACAGGAAUGUCUGAUUUAGGUAAAUACCUCUCACAAGUGGAGUAGGGGCGUAUCUGGUAGAGAACAGUGCUGAUUCCUUGGACUUGUGUGGCCUGGCCACCUGAGAGGUAGGUAGGAAGGUGUGUCUUGGCCAUGUCCUGGGGCCUCUGUAAACCUGAGAGGAUGGAGGAAGCUCUACUUUUUCUGACGAUGCUGUUGGUGAUAAUGAAGUAGGCUAUGAGAGCCCAUCUUCCAUUAAUUCAGAUGUUCCUAUACAGUUGGCCCUCUGUAAAUGGGAUUCUACAUUUGUAGAUUCAGCCAACUGUGGGUAAAAAUACUUGAAAAGAAACAAAAGUGUGUGUACUGAACAUGUACAUACUUUUUUCUUGCCAUUAUUCCCUAAACAUAAUAGUUUAACAACUAUUUAUGUAAUAUUUACAUUGUAUUAGGUAUUUAGUAAUCUAGAGAUGGUUUUAAAGCAGGGGUCCCUAGUCCCCAGGCCGUGGACUGGUACCCGUCUGUGGCCCGUUAGGAACUGGGCUGUACAGCAGGAGGUGAGCUCCGCCUCCUGUCAGAUUGGCAGCAGCAUUAGAUUCUCACGGAAGCGUGAACCCUAUUGUAAGCUGCACACGUGAGGGAUCUAGGUUGCACACUCCUUAAAAGAAUCUUUUUUUUUUGGAGACGGAGUCUCGUCUCACUGUGUUGCCUAGGCUGGAGUGCAGUGGCAUGAUCCUGGCUCACCUCAACCUCUGCCUCCCAGGUUCAAGUGAUUCUCCUGCCUCAGCUUCCUGAGUAGCUGGGAUUACAGGCACCUGCCUCCACACCCAGCUAAUUUUUGUAUUUUUAGUAGAAACAGGGUUUUACCAUGUUGGCCAGACUGGUCUCGAAUUCCUGACCUCAAGUGAUCUGCCUGCCUUGGCCUCCCAAAGUGCUGGGAUAUGAGCCACCAUGCCUGGCCAUCCUUAUGAGAAUCUAACUAAUGCCUGAUGAUCUGAGGUGGAACAGUUUCAUCCUGAAACCAUGUACCCUCUCCCCUCUUUGUGGAAAAACUGUCUUCCACAAAACCAGUCCCUGGUGCAAAAAAGUUGGAGACUGCUGGUUUAAAGUAUAUGGGAGAAUGUGUAUACGUUAUGUAAUAGUGUACCAUUUUAUAUCAGGGACUUGAGUCUUCGUGGAUUUUGGUAUCUGUUGGGGGUCCUGGAACUAAUCCUCCGUGGAUAUGGAGGAACAACUGUAUAUAUGGUCUCAGUAAUAAAUACGUAUCUGAGAUACCCUCUGUAUUAAGAAAAAAAAGAUGGGAAUUUCUUGGCUCAUAUAACUGAAUAGUUCCGAAAUUUGGGAAGGUCUGCCUGACUUAGGGCUUAGGUCAUGAGACUACAGUUCUUUCUUGGCUUUGACUUUUGUUUUUUGUAGUUGUUGACUCUGUUCUUUGAGGCUCUUCUCCAAGAUGGCUUCCAACAAGUCCUUGGGCAAACAUUUUUCCAGGUUUAGACCUAAGGGGAGAAGAGUGAGCAUUCUUGUCCUAGCAUUGCAGGAAACCUGAGAUUUUCACUGUGACUGCACUGAUUGUGGCCGUGUAUCUAACCCUGUACUGGUCACUAUGUCUAGGGAGAUGUACCUUGGUCAGGCCAGGGUCACAAGCAGCUUGAGUCAGCUUCCUCCAGUGUACUUGGUAGUUCUCAGAGAAGAGUUGGUGUGAAGUUCCCAAGAGAAGGGUGAAUUGACCCUGGGUGGCAAAAACAACAUAGCAUCUACUCUAGUGGGAUAAAGUAAGAUGGUAAGGCAUGGUGUUCAGGGUAUUUCUGAGUUUGGUUUGAUUCACAAAAUAGAUUGUGAACACUGUAAUUGCCCUUAAUUUUAGUUAACCUAUGUAAAUGUAAAUCUGUGAGGUGUCACUACAUUCUGCUAAAGCUUUGAUGGGCUCCUGCCAUAUUCUGGUUUGGCUUUUGUAUUAAAGAGCCAUUGUUGUUUUGGUUUCACUGUAUACAGGUAGACUUUUGUUUUAAUGAAUAGAGGUAUAAUCUGUUUUGAACAGGAAAAGCUGCUUUUGUAUUCUGGAUAAAGUUCAUACUAGUGGGAUUUCACCUAUGAAACUAAACAAAUCUUUGAAAAAUUUAAAAACCAUAUGUAUUUACACAGUGUCCAUUCAGUAGAAGUCGUUUAAAUAAAGGCUUCUGCCAAUAUAUGAAUAUUUAGAGCUGUAUUUUAUUAUUUUACUUUUUUUGAGACAGGGUCUCGCUCUGUCACCUAGGCUGGAGUGCAGUGGUGUGAAGACAGUUCACUGCAGUCUCCACCUCACAGGCUCAAGAGAUCCUCCCACCUCAGCUUCCUGAGUAGUUGGGACCACAGGUGUGCGCCACUACACCUGGCUUGCUUGCUUGCUUAUUUAUUGAUUUGAGAUGGGAGUCUCACUAUAUUGCCUAGGCUGGUCUUGAACUCCUGGGCUCAAUCCUCCAACCUUGGCCUCCCAAAAUGCUGGGUUUACAGGCUUGAACCACUGUACGUGGCCUUGAAUCUGUGUUUUAAUACUAUGCUUACUUGGCUGUGGUGUUGUGAAAAGAUCACUGAAAAUGGAGUCAGAGGCCUGAUUUGAGCCAGUCGUUUGUUGUGGGGGAAGGAGGUCAGGGGAGCUAACAUCUAAAGGCUCACUAUAUGCCAGGCACAGAACCAAGUGUGUUUGCAUGUAUAUUUCGUUUUUGUUGCCAGACUUUGAGGUAGGUUUUAUGGAUAAGGUCUUUAAGGCAAUAUCAGCUUCCUUUUAAAAAAGAAAUUCCGGAAACUGAGUUUUAGGCUGAAGAUCUCUAACUGGUAGUAGGGACAACUGAACCACAGGGUCCUAACUGACCCUGCGAUUUAUCUCCUUUUGCGGGGGGUUUCUUGAUAAUAGGGUGCACUUUACCUCAUUUUUUGGCUCAAGCAUGGAUAGGCCACCCUUCCUUUUCAUACCUAUAGCUAAGCUUUACAAAUGAUAUGCUGAUAAGAUACAAGCUACUCGUUAUUCAUGUGGGUUAAUAGACCUGUUUGUUUGCUUGUUUUUAAGUCUAUAGCCGCCCCACCCCCAAUCUACAAUUUCACCUUCUAAGGUUUUAGUUACUCAUUCAAACUGCAGUCUGAAAAUGUUACGAUAUUUUGAGAGAGAGAAGACUCUAGCUACGUAACUUUUGUAACAAUAUAUUGUUAUAAUUGUUCAUUUUACCAUUAGUUAUUGCUGUCAGUCUCUUACUGUGCCUUAUUUAUAAAUUAAACUUCAUGGGUAUGUACGUAUAGGAAAAAACAUGGUAUAUUUAGAGUUUAGUACUAUCUGCAGCUUUAGGCAUCCGCUGUGGGGUUGGCGGGGGGCGGUCUUGGGAGAUAAGUGGGGACUACUGUACAAUUAUCAGGCACACACAGGCUCUGGGAUUUUACAAAUGAGUAAAAGUGGUUCUUGCUGUUGAAGCACUUACAGUGGGAAUAGAGUGAAAUACAUGAAAAUGUGAUUUUAAUAUGUUAUAAAUGCUAUGAUGGUGGGAGUUUGUUUUGUGUAAAACAUCCUUUUAAUUGGUACUUUAAAUUUUAAUAUUCUUUCACAGGUCUACCUAUUUAGUCUUACACUUUCAAAGAACUACCUGGAUGCUGUAGAUUUUCAUGAUAUACUUUAUUAGAAUAAUCAUGGGCCAGACUGGGAAGAAAUCUGAGAAGGGACCAGUUUGUUGGCGGAAGCGUGUAAAAUCAGAGUACAUGCGACUGAGACAGCUCAAGAGGUUCAGACGAGCUGAUGAAGUAAAGAGUAUGUUUAGUUCCAAUCGUCAGAAAAUUUUGGAAAGAACGGAAAUCUUAAACCAAGAAUGGAAACAGCGAAGGAUACAGCCUGUGCACAUCCUGACUUCUGUGAGCUCAUUGCGCGGGACUAGGGAGUGUUCGGUGACCAGUGACUUGGAUUUUCCAACACAAGUCAUCCCAUUAAAGACUCUGAAUGCAGUUGCUUCAGUACCCAUAAUGUAUUCUUGGUCUCCCCUACAGCAGAAUUUUAUGGUGGAAGAUGAAACUGUUUUACAUAACAUUCCUUAUAUGGGAGAUGAAGUUUUAGAUCAGGAUGGUACUUUCAUUGAAGAACUAAUAAAAAAUUAUGAUGGGAAAGUACACGGGGAUAGAGAAUGUGGGUUUAUAAAUGAUGAAAUUUUUGUGGAGUUGGUGAAUGCCCUUGGUCAAUAUAAUGAUGAUGACGAUGAUGAUGAUGGAGACGAUCCUGAAGAAAGAGAAGAAAAGCAGAAAGAUCUGGAGGAUCACCGAGAUGAUAAAGAAAGCCGCCCACCUCGGAAAUUUCCUUCUGAUAAAAUUUUUGAAGCCAUUUCCUCAAUGUUUCCAGAUAAGGGCACAGCAGAAGAACUAAAGGAAAAAUAUAAAGAACUCACCGAACAGCAGCUCCCAGGCGCACUUCCUCCUGAAUGUACCCCCAACAUAGAUGGACCAAAUGCUAAAUCUGUUCAGAGAGAGCAAAGCUUACACUCCUUUCAUACGCUUUUCUGUAGGCGAUGUUUUAAAUAUGACUGCUUCCUACAUCGUAAGUGCAAUUAUUCUUUUCAUGCAACACCCAACACUUAUAAGCGGAAGAACACAGAAACAGCUCUAGACAACAAACCUUGUGGACCACAGUGUUACCAGCAUUUGGAGGGAGCAAAGGAGUUUGCUGCUGCUCUCACCGCUGAGCGGAUAAAGACCCCACCAAAACGUCCAGGAGGCCGCAGAAGAGGACGGCUUCCCAAUAACAGUAGCAGGCCCAGCACCCCCACCAUUAAUGUGCUGGAAUCAAAGGAUACAGACAGUGAUAGGGAAGCAGGGACUGAAACGGGGGGAGAGAACAAUGAUAAAGAAGAAGAAGAGAAGAAAGAUGAAACUUCGAGCUCCUCUGAAGCAAAUUCUCGGUGUCAAACACCAAUAAAGAUGAAGCCAAAUAUUGAACCUCCUGAGAAUGUGGAGUGGAGUGGUGCUGAAGCCUCAAUGUUUAGAGUCCUCAUUGGCACUUACUAUGACAAUUUCUGUGCCAUUGCUAGGUUAAUUGGGACCAAAACAUGUAGACAGGUGUAUGAGUUUAGAGUCAAAGAAUCUAGCAUCAUAGCUCCAGCUCCCGCUGAGGAUGUGGAUACUCCUCCAAGGAAAAAGAAGAGGAAACACCGGUUGUGGGCUGCACACUGCAGAAAGAUACAGCUGAAAAAGGACGGCUCCUCUAACCAUGUUUACAACUAUCAACCCUGUGAUCAUCCACGGCAGCCUUGUGACAGUUCGUGCCCUUGUGUGAUAGCACAAAAUUUUUGUGAAAAGUUUUGUCAAUGUAGUUCAGAGUGUCAAAACCGCUUUCCGGGAUGCCGCUGCAAAGCACAGUGCAACACCAAGCAGUGCCCGUGCUACCUGGCUGUCCGAGAGUGUGACCCUGACCUCUGUCUUACUUGUGGAGCCGCUGACCAUUGGGACAGUAAAAAUGUGUCCUGCAAGAACUGCAGUAUUCAGCGGGGCUCCAAAAAGCAUCUAUUGCUGGCACCAUCUGACGUGGCAGGCUGGGGGAUUUUUAUCAAAGAUCCUGUGCAGAAAAAUGAAUUCAUCUCAGAAUACUGUGGAGAGAUUAUUUCUCAAGAUGAAGCUGACAGAAGAGGGAAAGUGUAUGAUAAAUACAUGUGCAGCUUUCUGUUCAACUUGAACAAUGAUUUUGUGGUGGAUGCAACCCGCAAGGGUAACAAAAUUCGUUUUGCAAAUCAUUCGGUAAAUCCAAACUGCUAUGCAAAAGUUAUGAUGGUUAACGGUGAUCACAGGAUAGGUAUUUUUGCCAAGAGAGCCAUCCAGACUGGCGAAGAGCUGUUUUUUGAUUACAGAUACAGCCAGGCUGAUGCCCUGAAGUAUGUCGGCAUCGAAAGAGAAAUGGAAAUCCCUUGACAUCUGCUACCUCCUCCCCCCUCCUCUGAAACAGCUGCCUUAGCUUCAGGAACCUCGAGUACUGUGGGCAAUUUAGAAAAAGAACAUGCAGUUUGAAAUUCUGAAUUUGCAAAGUACUGUAAGAAUAAUUUAUAGUAAUGAGUUUAAAAAUCAACUUUUUAUUGCCUUCUCACCAGCUGCAAAGUGUUUUGUACCAGUGAAUUUUUGCAAUAAUGCAGUAUGGUACAUUUUUCAACUUUGAAUAAAGAAUACUUGAACUUGUC